GCGCAGAGCCCAGGCUGCGCUUCCCUGGUCAGGCACGGCACGUCUGGCCGGCCGCCAGGAUGCAGGCCCCGCACAAGGAGCACCUGUACAAGUUGCUGGUGAUUGGCGACCUGGGCGUGGGGAAGACCAGUAUCAUCAAGCGCUACGUGCACCAGAACUUCUCUUCGCACUACCGGGCCACAAUCGGCGUGGACUUCGCGCUCAAGGUGCUCCACUGGGACCCGGAGACUGUGGUGCGCCUGCAGCUCUGGGAUAUCGCAGGUCAAGAAAGAUUUGGAAACAUGACGAGGGUCUAUUACCGAGAAGCUAUGGGUGCAUUUAUUGUCUUCGAUGUCACCAGGCCAGCCACAUUUGAAGCAGUGGCAAAGUGGAAAAAUGAUUUGGACUCCAAGUUAAGUCUCCCUAAUGGCAAACCGGUUUCAGUGGUUUUGUUGGCCAACAAAUGUGACCAGGGGAAGGAUGUGCUCAUGAACAAUGGCCUCAAGAUGGACCAGUUCUGCAAGGAGCACGGUUUCGUAGGAUGGUUUGAAACAUCAGCAAAGGUUCUGGAGGUGGAGCUGACACUUGUUUCUUCUUUCAUAAACACGGGAUAAUGCUUUUCAUCCCAGAUGAAAGGGCUACACAAAGUGGUGAUAAGCAGAAGUCAGAGACCGUGACUUGGCCUUGUGUUGCUGGAAGCGCAAGUUGGCAGAGCCACAGGUUGCAGCCCUGGCAAGAUCAAGCAAAAGUUUCCUGUCUAUCACAUUUGAAAGUCUUUUUUCACAUCUAGGACUGGGCAUGUAGAUUCUUUUGUAGUCUGGACAAAUCAGUAGUUGUGCCAUCUUUUGUUAGGAUUUCUUGGCAAAUCUUUUGUAUCCUUUCUUUCAAAACUUCUAUAUCCUUAUAUUUUAGAUGUGGCUCUUGUGAACAACAUAUAGCUGAAUUUUGUCAUUGUUUUAUCCAAGCUGGCAAUGUUUUUCUUUAAAUUAGAUCACUUUCUUCAUUUACGUUAAAUGAAAUUACUUAUAUAUGUGGAUUUAAACCUAGGAUCUUAUUAUGUGCUUUCUGUUUGUCAUGCCAACUCUAUGUUCCUUUUUCUCUCUCAUAUUUCCUUCUAUUAAACUGACUUUUGGCAAUUCCAAUUCUUUCCCCUCUACCAAUUUAGAGGCUAUGUGCUCUAUUUCUAAUAUUUUCAUGGUUACUUUUUAACAUGCAUGUUUAAUUUAUGAAAAUCGAAUAUUAAUUGAUACCUUUAUUUUUACCCAUGAAAAUGCAAAGGAAUUAGAAUACUUUAUCAUCCCUCCUGAUAUAUGUAUUUUUGUAUUUUAUUUUUUAUCUUUUUAACUUUAUAGACAAAAUUGUAUGUAUUUAUCAAGUAAAACAUGAUGUUUGAAAUAUACAGUUUACUGAAAUAUACAUUACAUUGUAUUAUGGCUAAAGUAAGCUAAUUAACAUAUGCUUUAUUUCAUGCAAUGAAAACACUUAAAAUCUACUCUCUUAGACACCGUGUUCUACCUCAGAUCUCUUGAAAUUAUUCCUCCUAGCAAACUCAAAUUUUGUAAUCUUUGAGUAACAUCUUCCCAACUCCCUUAAUGACCAUCACGUCCACUCCUGGUGACCAUCAUUCUUCUUCCUUCUUCUAUGAGAUCAACAUUUUUACAUGUCACAUAUGAGUGAGAUCAUGAGGUAUUUGUCUUCCUAAGCCUAACAUAAUAUCCUUGAGGUUCAUCCAUUUUGUCACAAAUAACAGGAUAUUUUCUUUUUUAUGGUGGAAUAGUAUUUCAUUGUAUAUAUACAUCACAUUUUCUUUAUCCUUUCAUCUGUUAGUGGACACUUAGGUUGAUUUCAUAUCAUGGCUAUUGUGAAAAACACUGCACUAAACAUGGGAGCUUAGAUAUCUCUUCAAUAUUCUAGCUUCAUUUCCUUUGGAUAUAUACCCAAUAGUGAGAUUCCUCGAUCAUAUGGUAGUUCUAUAUUUACUUAUUUUUAGGAAUCUUCAUACUUUUUCUGUAAUAACUGUACUACUUUAUAUUCCUACCAAUAAUGUGCAAGUGUGAAAAUACCAAAUUAAGGUUUGUCCAUGAAAGGAUGAGAGACUGGGGAGGUAUAUGUACACUCUGUAGCUGAGACUCUGCAACACACAGUUCCUCUCUGUCAACUGGCUCUGCCAAUAGGACAUGCCAGAGGGAGAUAGAUAGAUAGGAAAAACAGACUUGUUUCUUCCUGUUAUUUUUCUUCCUGUUCCUACUGGUGUAAUCAUAGCAGUGACUUUGUUCUUGACCCUAGUGAGAGCAGCUGUUUGGUCCACAUUGCAGCUUUUCUAUACUAUCAGAACUACUCUCCUCAGAGAUAACAGCACCAGCCAUACAUUACUCCUUCCCAAAGGUCUUCGUCACACCUUUGUGAUUCCUCUUUUUCAAGUCUCUAAGAUUUAAUAAUUCCAUUCUCAUUCAUUUUUCCCUCAGGACUAGGACUGGUAGAUAUUUAUGUCCUACCACCUACCAUUAUGAUAUUCAUGUCCCUUUUGCUUUUUGUGUUCUGUCUACCUAGUUAACAAAAACAAUUUUUAUAUUAAAUUUUAUGUGUUAAAAUAGUCAGCAUGGUUUAUGUCUUGAAUGGUCCCUGACUGAAACAGAACUACUUUUACCCUUGAGAUAUUUAUAGAUCCAGUGAAGACAGCGUAGCUGUGCUAUGCUUUUUCCAGCCAUAAAGAACAAAGCCAUAGGCCUGUCAAACUUUCGAACUCUGGUAAAAUAAUCCACUUUAAUCUGGGACUUAGGGAUGUCCUGUAAGUAAGUUACUCCUUGUAUUAGGUCAUCUGUGUCAUGUGGAAAACUUUAAAUCUCAAACUUUGUUUGUAUUAGCAUUUUGGAGUUUUGAAGAAAAUAUUUUCUAUGCAUCAGCAGUCCCCAACCUUUUCGGCACCAGAGACUGGUUUCAUGGAAGACAAUUUUUCCACAGAUUUUUGUGGGGGAUGGUCUUGGGAUGAAAUUGUUCCACCUGAGAUCAUCAGGCAUUAGAUUCUCAAACGGACUAUGCAGUCUAGAUCUCUUGCAUACACAGCUCACAAUAGAGUUCGCGCUCCUAUGAGAAUCUAAUACCCCACUGAUCUGACAGGAGGUGGAGCUCAGGCAGUGGUGCUCACUCACUUGCCACUCACCUCCUGGUGUGCAGCCUGGUUCCUAACAGGCUAUAGUCUUGUACCAGUCCAGAUCCAGAAUUUCAUUUGUCUCAAAUAUCUAGCCAGCCAUCAGGGAAAAUGGAAUACCUGACUAAAUGCCUUGUAAGAUUUCAGGACUAAAAACAUUUCAUUGUUAGCAGUACAUUCUUCACUCACUUGUUUUCUCUUUAAAUCUUUGAUAAGCUCAGUGCAACAUUGAUUAAUAAACAAUAAAAUACUUGUCUUGAUUUAAAUAUUUUACCUUACUCUGCCACUGUCAUAAAUAUUUUUUUCAGUUAUAUCUGGUAGUAUUUUAAAAUAUUUCAAAAAGGAAAACAAAUAAAAAAAUUAAGAAUACAAAUGAAACAGGAUAUAAAUGCUUAGGAAUUUUUUUCCCUAAUUUCUGGCAUUGAUAUAAUAGCAUGCUUCUAUACUCUGAAUGUUUGUAGGCCCCCAAAAUUCAUAUGUUGAACCAGAUAUUCCCAAUGUAACAGUAUUAGAGAAUGGAGCCUUUGAGAGAUGAUUAGGUCACAGGAACUCUGCCCUCAUUAAUAAGAGUAAUGCCCUUAUAAAAGAGACCUCAGGGAGCUCUUUCAUCGUAUGAGGAUGUGGUAAGAAGGUGCCACCUAUGAAGCAAAAACAGACCCUCACCAGACACUGAAUCUGCUGGUGCCCUGAUCUUGGAUUGCUUAGCCUCUAGAACUGUAAGAGAUUAAAUUUCUCCCAUUUACAAGCCAUGAAGUUUAUGGCAUUUUUUAGAGCAGCCUGAAUGGACUAAGCUGCAUAUCAUGAAGUCUCUAUCUUUUAAGAGAAGAUCCUUUCUGUCAAAAAAACAUAUUCAUAACUCUCUACAAAUUUAUCAGUUAUCACACUUUAAUUUUCUGUUUACUUGCUCUGAUGGCUAAUUUUAUGUAUCAACCUGACUAGGCUACAGUAGCCAGUUUUUGGUCAAACUUCAGUCUAGAUGUUACUGUGAGGGUUAUUUUUUUAGAUCUGAAUAACAUUUAAAUUAGUAGACUUUGAGUGAAGUAAAUUAUCUCCAAUAACGUGGGGAGGCCCACUAAACCAGUUGAAGGCUUUAAGAGAAAAAGACUGAGGUCCCUAAGAAAGAAGAAAUUCUACCUCUAGGCUGCCUUUUGACCUGAACUGCAGCAUCAACUCUUUCCUGGUCUCUAUCCUGGGUUUCCAACCUGCAUGUGUAUAUCUGUAUAUAUAUACACACAUAUAUGUAUGUGUAUAUAUGUAUGUGUGUGUAUAUAUGUGUGUGUAUACACAUAUAUGUAUGUGUAUAUGUAUAUACACACAUGCAUGUAUAUAUACACAUACAUAAAUGUGUAUAUGUGUGUGUGUGUGUGUGUGCGUGUGUGUGUGUGUGUGUAGUGUUUUCUCUGUGGAACCCUGACUAAAAUGCUUGCCAAUCACUCCCUCCCUCUAUCCUAUGGUUCUUUUGUGAGCAGAGAUUAUAUCUUCUCCAGUGUCUGCUACAAUUCUGACAUCUAGAGAGAGCUCAAUAAUAUUUGUCAAGCAAAUUAACAAAGGAUAGCUAUUAAGAUGCCUGAGCAUUUAGCCAUCAGGAAAAAAAAUGACAUAGAUAAUAUCUUCUAACAUGAAAAUGAUAAAGAGAAUAAAAAUAUAAUAUGUGUGUGUGUACCUGUGAAUAUGUGUAUAUGCAUAGGUGUUUGUGUGUGUGUAUAAACAUAGAUGUCCAUAGAUAGUUGCACAUAUGGAUGGAAGUAAGAACAAAAGAAAAGGAUAUUAUUAAAUAAAAAGGAAGAUUUUUAAAAUGUUACCAAGCAGGCUCUUUCACACUCCAGAUACACCAAUGCUUCUUUGUACUACCCUUUUAACACCAUUUAGGCAGAAAGUGAAAAGUAGCUUUUCAGUGCCCUCUGAGGGAGGGCAUAUAUUGCUUAGAACACAGAGUCAAAAUGUUGGCAUUAAGUUCCAAAACAGGCUUUUAAAAUUCAUUGAAGAAGCAACAACCUUGAAAGCAGAGGUUUUCACAAGGCUGAGAUAUUGAGAGACAAACGACUUUUUUUGAAUUCAAAUUCAAAGGCGGAAAGUUUAAGCUAAAAAUGAUAACACUGAGAAAAAUCAUGACAAUUGUAACAGUUUUGUUUACAUGGAAUGAAGAAAUAAAAUCAUUUCAUCAUUAGAGGAGUAUUUUUAUCAUGUAAACAGAAAAUGGAGCAAUAUAGUAAGUGACUUAUGGAUUAUAUAGAAAUAAUUCAUGGCCUUCAACUUUGAAGUAUACAGCAGAUAUCCCAGCAGAAGGAGAUGAUGGAAUUCCCAGAUAAGUUUUGGAGGGCACCAUAAGAAAGGUAUUUCUUGCCUUACUUCCGAGACUGAAAACCCUGUAGAGAAGCUAACUGUCUGGUGAGGUUAUGCACAAUAAGAUUAAAAAAAAAAAUCUGAGUGGAAUACCUAGGCAGAUGGGCCUAAGACCAUCAGCAAAAUUUAAGUCCUCACAGGGUUGUAUAAAAUCUUCCUGUCCUAUGUCCCAGGGAGAAGCACAAAGGCUGAAGAGGCAGAAUGUGGGCUGUUGACCAGUGAUCAUGGUGAAAACAAGAUACCUCAGCAGGUGUCAGUGUAUGCAGGCAAAUGCCCUAAGACUAGUGCUGAAGACACCCACAGAGAACAGAGGACAAUGAUGGGCCAGAUACCUUGAUCUAGUUAAUGCUAGGACAAUGCAUACACCCACUGCCUCUACCCAACUCAGCAUUUAGAUUACUCAUUGGAGAGAGGUAGAAAGUAAAGAAAGUAAAAACAAAGGGGAAACCCCUCAAUUAGACUAUUUUCCUAAAGAAGACAAAUAAAUGUCUGCAAAUGACUCAAUUUACCUGGAUGUAAAUAUACCAAGAAAUUUGCUAUUUACCAAAAGGAAGAGUUAAACCUAGUUGGUUCAGUUACAAAACAAUAAAAUCACGGUUUUGGUCACCCAAGUUGCAUCAGAGUGAAAAAUUCAGACCUGGCAUAUGCAUAUGUGGAAGUACACACAUUCACUCAGUCACAGUGUGCAAAGUAACUAUCAGAUCAAAGAGAAAGAGAAAGUAUGGCUCUCAAGGGCAGGGCAUGGGCCACAGAAAGUUAUUCUCAGGCCUUGGGGCCUAACGGAAUUUGCUUUGCUGAGUUUUGAACUUGCUUGGGACAAAUGACCCUUUAUUCCUUCCAUCUUCUCCUUUUCACGAUGUCAGUGUCUAUCCUAUGCCUGCCCUACCACUGUAUCUUGGAAGCAGAUACUUGUUUUGUAGUUUCACAGGUCUGUGAA